ACACUCAAGCUCUCACACGCACGCAUGGCCCCCAUGGCUGACUCGGUGCUCAACCACUCCUGGCCGGCCUUCUCCAAGCUGUGGCUGAAGCGGUGGGCCUUCAAGAGAGGCUCUGAGCCCAAGUCAUGUGUCCAGCCUUUUGACUCUGGAGCUGUGGCUUCAGCCACCAAGAGCAGCAGUGGAUCCUGGAAACCUGAGAACCCAGACUUCUUCUCUGCCAUGGGGGAUGAUCAGGAGGAUGAUUUUCCCAGGCGGCUCAGCGAGAGUAUGGAGGACCUCAGCCUGGAUUUGGGGGCCCUUCAGGGCAGCGAGUAUCUGCAGGACCUGGGCCUUGGGGCCCCUUCCCACAGCCAGCCUGGGGAGACCCCAGACAGCCGCCCCACCGGUGAAGAACCAGGAAGAGAUUCUCUUUUCUCCAGCUUGGCAGGGUCCCAAGACCUGUCAAGGCGGCGCAGCUGGGAAAGGUCGCGGAGCUGCUCAGAGAGCUGGCGGAGGCUCAGCCUCGAUGCCUCAGCUGUGGAUGAGGAACCCUGUCUCCCCCGAACACUGGCCAGCCUUGCUUUGAACCUGCCAGGAGGAGGGCUGAAGACCUGGACUCAAGGGUGUCUCUCUGGGGGCGGGACCCCCGCAGAGAGCCCAGGCAAGGAAUGUGACAGCCCCAAGAAAAGAGGGAGGUCAAGGUCCGUUCCUGUGUCCUUCUAUGAGAUCCGCUCUCCGGAAAUCUCUCCGGGUUUGGAAGUGCCCACUCCACCUGUUCAAGGCCUGGAACCUCCAGUGCUGGAGUGCAUGGAAAAAGACCAUGUGGAACCAGAUCACGUGCUGAUUGUCCAGCAGGUGCUUCAAGAACUUCGACAGUACCAUGGGGCCCGGCAGAGGGCUUGCAUGUCAGCCAGCCCCGGAGGAGCCCACUCGAACCUGACCUGGUUUGAAUUCCUGUCGGAGAGCGAGGACGGUGCUGGCAAGAACGAGAAGAGUGACAAGAGUACCAGUGUGAAGCGCAGGCUGAGCUGCCUCCGCAGUCGAGUGACCAGGCAGAAGGAGAAGGGGAAGAGCCCAGCACAUCUGAAGGACAAGGGCCAGGAUGCACGAGAGAGGCGGGAGUGUGUCAAUGGGCACCAGCUGUUGCAAGGGACCUUCUCCGGCCCCUCCAGCUGCCCCCUGUGUGGCAAACCUUUCUUGAGCUCAGCCUCGCUCAAGGAGCACCCCCGGGGCACCCUCCUGUCCGAUGGCAGCCCGGCCCUGUCCAGGAAUGUCGGUAUGACGGUCUCUCAGAAAGGGGGUCCCCAGCCAACACCGAGCCCGGCUGGCCCUGGGACGCAACUCGGACCAAUCACAGGAGAGAUGGAUGAAGCCGAUUCUGCGUUUUUAAAAUUUAAGCAGACAGCUGAUGACUCUCUGUCCCUUACAUCUCCAAACACCGAGUCCAUUUUUGUAGAAGAUCCCUACACCGCCUCGCUGAGGAGUGAGAUUGAGUCAGACGGCCACGAGUUUGAAGCUGAGUCCUGGAGCCUCGCCGUGGAUGCAGCCUACGCCAAGAAGCAAAAGAGGGAGGUGGUGAAAAGACAAGAUGUCCUUUAUGAGCUGAUGCAGACAGAGGUGCACCACGUGCGGACGCUCAAGAUCAUGCUGAAGGUGUACUCCAGGGCCCUGCAGGAGGAGCUGCAGUUCAGCAGCAAGGCCAUUGGCCGCCUCUUCCCAUGCGCUGACGACCUGCUGGAGACGCACAGCCACUUCCUCGCUCGGCUCAAGGAGCGCCGCCAGGAGUCCCUGGAGGAGGGCAGUGACCGGAAUUAUGUCAUCCAGAAAAUCGGCGACCUCCUGGUUCAGCAGUUUUCAGGUGAAAAUGGGGAGAGAAUGAAAGAAAAGUACGGUGUGUUUUGUAGUGGCCACAAUGAAGCUGUUAGUCAUUACAAGUUGCUGCUUCAGCAAAACAAGAAAUUUCAAAACUUGAUCAAGAAAAUUGGCAACUUCUCCAUCGUGCGGCGGCUUGGCGUGCAGGAGUGCAUUCUCCUGGUUACACAACGCAUAACCAAAUACCCAGUGCUGGUGGAGCGCAUCAUCCAGAACACGGAAGCUGGCACUGAGGACUAUGAAGACCUGACCCAGGCCUUGAACCUCAUCAAAGAUAUCAUCUCACAAGUGGACGCCAAGGUCAGUGAGUGUGAGAAGGGCCAGCGCCUCAGGGAGAUCGCAGGGAAGAUGGACCUGAAGUCUUCCAGCAAACUCAAGAACGGGCUCACCUUCCGCAAGGAAGACAUGCUUCAGCGGCAGCUCCACCUGGAGGGCAUGCUAUGCUGGAAGACCACAUCAGGGCGCUUGAAAGAUAUCCUGGCUAUCCUGCUGACCGACGUACUUUUGCUGCUACAAGAAAAAGAUCAGAAAUACGUCUUUGCUUCUGUGGACUCAAAGCCACCCGUCAUCUCGUUACAAAAGCUCAUCGUGAGGGAAGUGGCCAACGAGGAGAAAGCGAUGUUUCUGAUCAGCGCCUCCUUGCAAGGGCCGGAGAUGUAUGAAAUCUACACGAGCUCCAAAGAGGACAGGAACGCCUGGAUGGCCCACAUCCAAAGGGCUGUGGAGAGCUGCCCUGACGAGGAGGAGGGGCCCUUCAGCCUGCCCGAAGAGGAAAGGAAGGUGGUCGAGGCCCGCGCCACGAGACUCCGGGACUUUCAAGAGCGGUUGAGCAUGAAAGACCAGCUGAUCGCACAGAGCCUCCUAGAGAAACAGCAGAUCUACCUGGAGAUGGCCGAGAUGGGCGGCCUCGAAGACCUGCCCCAGCCCCGAGGCCUAUUCCGUGGAGGGGACCCAUCCGAGACCCUGCAGGGGGAGCUAAUUCUCAAGUCGGCCAUGAGCGAGAUCGAGGGCAUCCAGAGCCUGAUCUGCAGGCAGCUGGGCAGCGCCAACGGCCAGGCGGAAGACGGAGGCAGCUCCACAGGCCCGCCCAGGAGGGCUGAGACCUUCGCGGGCUACGACUGCACAAACAGCCCCACCAAGAAUGGCAGUUUCAAGAAGAAAGUCAGCAGCACUGACCCCAGGCCCCGAGACUGGCGAGGCCCCCCAAACAGCCCGGACUUGAAGCUCAGUGACAGUGACAUUCCUGGGAGCUCUGAGGAAUCGCCGCAGGUGGUGGAGGCGCCAGGCACGGAAUCCGAUCCCCGUCUGCCCACCGUCCUGGAGUCGGAGCUUGUCCAGCGGAUCCAGACACUGUCCCAGCUGCUCCUGAACCUUCAGGCGGUAAUCGCCCACCAGGACAGCUAUGUGGAGACGCAGCGGGCUGCCAUCCAGGAGCGGGAGAAGCAGUUCCGGCUGCAGUCGACGCGUGGGAACCUGCUGCUGGAGCAGGAGCGGCAACGCAACUUCGAGAAGCAGCGGGAGGAGCGCGCGGCCCUGGAGAAGCUGCAGAGCCAGCUGCGGCACGAGCAGCAGCGCUGGGAGCGCGAGCGCCAGUGGCAGCACCAGGAGCUGGAGCGUGCGGGCGCGCGGCUGCAGGAGCGCGAGGGCGAGGCGCGGCAGCUACGCGAGCGGCUGGAGCAGGAGCGGGCCGAGCUGGAGCGCCAGCGCCAGGCCUACCAGCACGACCUGGAGCGGCUGCGCGAGGCCCAGCGUGCCGUGGAGCGCGAGCGGGAGCGCCUGGAGCUGCUGCGCCGCCUCAAGAAGCAGAACACCGCGCCAGGCGCGCUGCCGCCCGACACACUGGCCGAGGCCCAGCCCCCAAGCCACCCUCCCAGCUUCAACGGGGAAGGGCUGGAGGGCCCUCGUGUGAGCAUGCUGCCAUCCGGCGUGGGGCCAGAGUACGCAGAGCGCCCCGAGGUGGCUCGCCGGGACAGCGCCCCCACCGAGAACCGGCUGGCCAAGAGCGAUGUGCCCAUCCAGCUGCUCAGCGCCACCAACCAGUUCCAGAGGCAGGCGGCCGUGCAGCAGCAGAUCCCCACCAAGCUGGCGGCCUCCACCAAGGGUGGCAAGGACAAGGGCGGCAAGAGCAGGGGCUCUCAGCGCUGGGAGAGCUCAGCGUCCUUCGACCUGAAGCAGCAGCUGCUGCUCAACAAGCUCAUGGGGAAAGAUGAGAGCACCUCACGGAACCGCCGCUCGCUGAGCCCUAUCCUGCCCGGCAGACACAGUCCUGCGCCCCCACCAGACCCUGGCUUCCCCGCCCCGAGCCCACCGCCAGCUGACAGCCCCUCCGAGGGCUUCUCUCUCAAGGCCGGGGGCACAGCCCUCCUGCCCGGGCCCCCAGCUCCCUCGCCACUGCCGGCCACACCACUCAGCGCCAAGGAGGACGCCAGCAAAGAAGACGUCAUCUUCUUCUAAAAGGGCCGUGACUCAAGCUUUCUCAAGGCACGACAGGCCCCCUCUUCCUCAUCUUGAUUUGGAUACAAGACGCCAGCUGGCAGGCAGGAGGUGCUGCUGAAGCCCUGCACGGCCCCUGAAAACUGUCACGGCUCAGGAGCUCCAGGCUGAGGCCUGGGGGACCUCGCAUCAGUCCCUCCACCCACCCUGCCCAUGGGUUUCACCACAGGCAGCUCCAUGAGAGCCCCGGCCCCUGCCCUGGCGGCUUCUGCUUUGCGGGAAGGGCCCUCCGUGGGCUCUGGCUGUGUCCCUGUGCUCUUCCGGCAGUGUCAGGGGGUAGUGGCCUCGGCCUGGCCGCCGGCCCGGGCCGCCUGGUACAUGCUGAGGAUUGAGGAGAUGGUGCCCAUGAGGCCCACUAGCCACGGCGGGAAGCGGCCGGCCCACAGCACGCCCCGGGGCAGCCAGUGCACGGCGUUGGCCAGGUCGGCCAGGUUGCUGAGAAGUGACAGCGCCUCCGACUGCAUCUGCGCCUCCAUGGCCCUCCGCUUGCCCCGGGGCAGCGGGCUGUGGGGCAGAGAGGGGCCGCUUACACUCACGCUCACACCUGCCUGCCCUUCCCAAGCCCCUGAAUGCCCUGUGUGGCCUGGCAGCCCUGAGCCCCUGCCUGUGAGUGGGAGGAGCUGGCAGGACUGAGGUGGCCUCCCUGACCAUCCACAGAGACUGAGUCCCCAUCACCCCCCCGACCCAAGCACGAACAGGGCAGGAACCCGGGUCCAAGUCCUCAAAUCCACACCUCACUCCUCGUCCUGAACACCCAGAGAUGGGGAUUCCUUGUGAAAAACAGAAAGCACAAAUGCACUUUGGGAGGUGUGGAGGGAAGGGGGAACCCCCAGGAGCGUGGCCUGUGCCUGCCCGGCCUUUCUUUAUCAGGAUGACACAGUGACGAUAAGCCUGGCCAAUAUGGCGAGACCCCAUCUCCACCAAAAAAUAAAAAACAAAAUUAGCCAGGCGUGCUGGCCCGUGCCUGUAGUCCCAGCUACUCGGGAAGCUGAAACAGGAGGAUCAGUUGAGCCCAGGAGGCAGAGGCUGCAGUGAGCCAAGAUGGCACCACUGUGCUCCAGCCUGGGCAACAGAGCAAGACCCUGUCUCAAAAAACAAAAAGAAAAAGCAACAGUAACAAUGGCCAUGGCCUUCGGGAAAUUGAUCAUUCUCUCCUGCUGGGGGCGCAGCCAUGAAGGCUCAGCCCUGGAGUCCCCGCUCAAGCAAGCCUCAGUUUCUCCAUCUGUAAAAGGUACCGCCACCCACCAGAGGCUGUGAUGACUCCCCCAUGACCUGAGCACAACAGUCCCCAGCAUGGGCCUGCACAGGGGUGGCUGCGAGCCGGGAUCCCACGCCUGCUGGAGGGAGUGGGCCUCCCUGCUGGGUGAUCACGGGCUCCUACCUGGUGAAGGGCGCCGUGGGGCUCCGCAGCCUCUGUCUCAGUUUCAGCAGCAUCCACAGGGACCUGCAGCACCAGAGCCCGAGGGAGGAUGCCCCGGCGGGGAGCAGGAGGGUUAGCUCCACAACGCUGGCCCCGGACAUACAGUCUGGGACAGGUGCUGCAUCUCGGAUAAACGGCCUGCCCUCUCCCUGCCCCCACAGUCCCACACCCUCCUGGCUGUGCCUCAUGCUCCCGGGGACUCAUCUCUAACACGGCCCCGUCCCACCCGGGACAUCGUCCUGCACUUCUGACGUGGCCAUCCAGGGCCUGGCCCAGCCUCUGCAAACCACUGGCAAGUGCUCAAAGGAACAUCAAGCCCCGUGAGGUGUUCACAGCCUGGCAGGGAGUCCUACACAGAAAAGGAUGCCAAGAGGCCCGCAGUUGGACAGGCGUGGGGACGCCGUUUCCCCUCCGGGCCUCAGCUGCCUUGUCUGCUCUGUGUGGAAAGGUCCAAAUCAGUGCCAUGCCAGCACCCCCUGCACACACACCCCGGACAUUGGCUGGACCUGUCUGGAUGAUCCCCUGGGCCCCCAGGGCUGGCAUCUGCAGGCUGAGGAAGGGGCUACCCAGUGGGCAGCCUCUGUGCUCCCAGCAGGCUCUGCAGCCGUGCAUGGCACCCACCCGGGCCAGUCCACCAGGCACCUGCACUCUCCAGCCUCGGCCGUGGGGUGUGCCGGGUUGUGACUGUGACAGAAUGGGCAGGGCCUGGUCACAACUCCUCUGGCCACUGGGUACCCAGGGUGCAGGAUGCAGGAUAGCGCCAGUGGCACAGCAGGUGGGAGCCUCCUGGGGGGCUAGGGAAAAACACUGAUUCCUGGGCUCCCCAGACCCACAGAAUCAGAAGCUCUGGGCCAAGCGCGAUGGCUCACACCUGUAAUCCCGGGACUUUGGGAGGCCAAGGCCGGUGGAUCACCUGAGGUCAGGAGUUCAAGACUAGCCUGGCCAACAUGGUGAACCCCUGUCUCUACUAAAAAUACAAAAAUUAGCUGGGGGUGGUGGUGGGCGCCUGUAAUCCCAGGUACUCGGGAGGCUGAGGCAGGAGAAUCACUUGACCCCGGGAGGUGGAGGUUGCAGUAAGCCAAGAUCGCACCACUGCACUCCAGCCUGGGCGACAGAGGAAGACUGUGUCUCAAGAAAAGAAUCAGAAGCCCUGGGCGCCGGACCCAGGCAUCUCCAUUUAGCAACCUCCUGGCUGAUGCUCCGGCAGCCCUGGGCCUUAGGGCAGAUGUCUGGUCAUGAUGAGCACACAUGGAAUGCUCUCCACCCACUCCCCCUGCUCACUGCAAAUCCAGAGAAAUGAUGAAAAACCACAUGCCCGAAACAAGAAUGCCGCAGCAGGCGGGGCACACAGGACUUCGAUGGCCGUGAAACAAUUCCAUUUGAUUCUGCAAGGGGGGACACGUGUCAGUGUCCAAACCCAUAGGAUGCCCAAAACCUAGCGUGAACCCUAACGUGAGCUACUCACUUGGGGUGAUGAUGGAUCCAUGGAGGGGCAUCAGUUGUAACAAAUGCACCAUGUGGAUGCUGCCAGUAGUCGGGGAGGCUGUGUGUGGGGGUAUAUGGGAGCUCUCUGAACGUUAUGCUCAAUUUUGCCAUGAGCCUAAAACUGCUCUAAAAAAAUAAAGUCUGGGCCGGGA